AGACCACUGGGACAAUUCAGUAUGGCAAAGGUGACCAGUGAGCCACAGAAGCCUAAUGAAGAUGUGGACGAACAGACCCCAUCAACCUCAAGUACCAAAGGGAGGAAGAAGGGGAAGACACCCCGUCAACGAAGGUCCAGAAGCGGCGUUAAGGGCCUAAAGACCACCAGGAAGGCGAAAAGACCCCUUCGAGGGAGCUCGAGCCAAAAAGCCGGUGAAACUAACACCCCUGCAGGAAAACCUAAGAAAGCUAGAGGACCAAUACUGCGUGGUCGUUAUCACCGGCUGAAAGAAAAAAUGAAGAAAGAAGAGGCCGACAAAGAGCAAAGCGAGACCUCAGUUCUGUGAUGUCUCUAGAGGUCCGCCACUGAAAAGUCAUCAAUCAUACAGUCAGUGAAUUCUACACCAACAGGUUAAAACCAUGAAAAUAAAAUCAACCUGAAUCGAAAGG